CUUAAGGGCGGGAGUCUCGGUUUGUGGUGGCUUCGCUGAGGCAGUGGUGGCCGCACUAUACCGUUAGAAACUCAAUUUCCCGGAGGUUGUGAGGCCCUUUGAGGCGAAAUCGCUCUGGGCGUGAAAGGAGCAGGCGUUGGCAAUGGAAGGACCACCGCGACCUCAGGCUGACCGUAGGGAGGGAUCUUGAGGGCCCUCCGAGUCCCCUGGGCUUGCGCUUUCUUUCUUUGCAGCCACCGUGCCUACCGCGAGGAUGAGCUCGGCCUCGGUCACCGCUUUCGAGAAGGAGCAUCUCUGGAUGUAUCUGCAGGCGCUCGGCUUCGAGCCAGGCCCGGCAACCAUUGCCUGCGGAAAGAUCGUGUCGCACACGCACCUCGGAGUGAACAUGUUUGACAAGCUGAACCGUGAUGCCUUUCAUAUAAUUUCUUAUUUUUUGUUUCAAGUUCUGGACCAGUCUCUCACCAAAGAAGUUUUCAAAUUUUGUUGGCCCCCAUUUGACCAAAAAAGUGACACUGAAUUCCGAAAACAUUGCUGUGAAUGGAUAAAAAGGAUUUCUGGUGAAUGUGGAAGUAGCUUUCCUCAAGUUGUUGGUUCACUAUUUCUUUCUCCUGGUGGUCCUAAGUUUAUUCAUCUGAUGUAUCAUUUUGCAAGAUUUGUUGCAAUGAAAUAUAUUAAAUCCAAUUCUAAAAAUUCUUCUCAUCAUUUUGUAGAGACAUUUAACAUAAAACCACAGGACUUGCACAAAUGCAUUGCCAGAUGCCAUUUCGCACGUAGCAGAUUUUUACAAAUUUUGCAAAGACAAGAUUGUGUUACCCAAAAAUAUCAGGAAAAUGCACAAUUAUCAGUUAAGCAGGUACGAAACUUGAGAUCUGAAUGUAUAGGAUUGGAAAACCAAAUAAAGAAAAUGGAACCCUAUGAUGACCACAGUAAUAUGGAAGAAAAAAUUCAAAAGGUUCGGUCUUUGUGGGCUUCAGUGAAUGAAACGCUCAUGUUUUUGGAAAAAGAGAGAGAAGUUGUUAGUUCGGUCCUUAGUCUUGUUAACCAAUAUGCUUUAGAUGGAACUAAUGUUGCUAUUAAUAUUCCAAGGCUCUUACUUGACAAAAUUGAGAAACAAAUGUUUCAGUUGCACAUAGGAAAUGUUUAUGAGGCUGGAAAACUGAACCUCUUAACAGUUAUUCAGUUAUUAAAUGAAGUCUUGAAGGUGAUGAAAUAUGAACGUUGUCAGGCUGAUCAAGCAAGAUUGACGGUAGACCUUCACUACCUUGAAAAAGAGACCAAAUUUCAGAAGGAAAGAUUAUCAGAUCUGAAACAUAUGAGGUAUAGAAUAAAAGAUGAUCUCACAACUAUAAGACAUUCUGUUGUUGAAAAGCAAGGAGAAUGGCAUAAAAAGUGGAAAGAAUUUCUUGGUUUGUCUCCUUUCAGUCUAAUUAAAGGUUGGACUCCAUCUGUAGAUCUUUUACCACCAAUGUCUCCCCUUUCGUUUGAUCCUGCCUCAGAAGAAGUGUAUGCAAAGAGUAUUCUUUGUCAGUAUCCUGCUUCACUUCCAGAUGCACAUAAGCAACAUAACCAAGAAAAUGGUUGCAGAGGAGACAGUGAUACCUUGGGAGCGCUACAUGAUCUAGCCAACAGCCCUGCCUCUUUCUUGUCGCAGUCAGUUUCAUCAUCAGAUAGAAACAGUGUUACAGUACUUGAAAAGGACACAAAGAUGGGAACUCCCAAAGAAAAAAAUGAAGCAAUUUCUAAGAAAAUACCAGAAUUUGAAGUGGAAAAUUCUCCAUUAUCAGAUGUUGCAAAGAAUACAGAGAGUAGUGCAUUUGGAGGGUCUUUGCCAGCUAAAAAAAGUGAUCCAUUUCAAAAAGAGCAAGAUCAUCUGGUAGAAGAGGUUGCCAGAGCAGUUUUAUCUGAUUCACCACAGCUCUCUGAAGGAAAAGAAAUAAAAUUAGAGGAACUAAUUGACUCUCUGGGUUCUAACCCCUUCUUAACAAGGAAUCAGAUUCCCCGUACUCCAGAAAACUUGAUAACUGAAAUUAGGAGCUCAUGGAGAAAAGCUAUUGAAAUGGAAGAAAACAGAACUAAAGAACCAAUUCAAAUGGAUGCUGAACAUAGAGAAGUAUUGCCAGAAUCAUUACCUGUGUUGCACAAUCAAAGAGAAUUUAGCAUGGCUGAUUUUCUCUUAGAAACCACUGUAUCAGAUUUUGGCCAGUCUCAUUUGACUGAAGAGAAAGUUAUUUCAGAUUGCGAGUGUGUGCCUCAGAAACAUGUGCUGACCAGUCACAUAGAUGAACCACCAACACAAAAUCAGUCAGAUUUGUUAAAUAAGAAAGUAAUUUGCAAGCAAGAUUUGGAAUGUUUAGCCUUCACCAAGCUUUCAGAAACUAGCCGAAUGGAGACAUUCUCCCCUGCUGUCGGCAAUAGGAUAGAUGUGAUGGGUGGCAGUGAAGAGGAGUUUAUGAAAAUAUUGGACCACUUAGAAGUUUCUUGUAACAAACCUUCCACAAAUAAAACUAUGUUGUGGAAUUCUUUUCAGAUAUCAAGUGGAAUUAGUUCUAAGAGUUUUAAAGAUAAUGAUUUUGGCAUAUUACACGAAACUCUCCCGGAAGAAGUUGGUCAUCUAAGUUUUAAUAGUUCCAGUAGUUCAGAGGCCAAUUUUAAACUGGAGCCAAAUAGUCCUAUGCAUGGUGGCACUCUUCUAGAAGAUGUUGUGGGAGGGAGACAGACUACUCCAGAAUCAGACUUUAAUUUACAGGCUCUUCGCAGUAGAUACGAGGCUCUGAAGAAAUCUCUUUCCAAGAAAAGGGAAGAAUCUUACCUCUCGAAUUCCCAAACACCCGAAAGACACAAACCAGAAUUGAGCCCUACUCCCCAAAAUGUACAAACAGAUGAUACGCUUAACUUUUUGGACACCUGUGAUUUGCAUACUGAGCAUAUAAAGCCAUCUUUACGCACGUCCAUCGGUGAAAGAAAACGGUCUCUUUCACCACUAAUUAAGUUUUCUCCAGUGGAACAAAGAUUGAGAACCACAAUAGCAUGUAGUCUUGGAGAACUACCUAAUUUAAAGGAAGAAGACAUUUUGAAUAAGAGCCUUGAUGCAAAAGAACCACCGUCUGACUUGACAAGAUGAAGACGUACCCAUUUAAUAUAACUAUGAUGCACUUAAAUUGAAGCUAUGCCACAGGAUAGAAAAUGAAUUACAACUUAAAUACAUGUUGGAAGUGUAACACUGUUUUUCAAGGUUUAAAAAAAUUCCUAAUGCCUUUUAGCCUUCUUUAAUAUUUUUAGGUAAGGAAAGUAUGUUUGGAUUUUUUCCUCUUUGUAGGUAUAUGAGAUUGAAAUGUGAAGUAUUUGGACAACAAACGUCAAGCAAUGGGAAGCCAUUUUGAUUUCUUGAGUAAUCUUGUAAGCAUUAAGUGAAUGACAAAGUAGUAGUGUAACUUAUUUCUUAUGUUAUAACUUCAGUCAAUUAAUAUAAGGAUAGUUUUUGUUGUAUGUUCACUAAAUGGUUAAUAUAAUAGCCAUUGAAUAUACUAAUCUUUCAUCUUAGAGAACUAUACAACUUUUAUUGUUUCUUAAUGGAACAUUCUGGCUAACCAGAAAAAGUGAGAAAAGUAGUACCUUGGGAUGUGUAGUCAAGAUGACAAAUUUUAAGACUGGAAAAGCUCUAAACAGGCUUAAUGAUUCUUCAGGUAGAAUGAUCCUGAGAAGUGAUGUUUGAUGGAAUAAAGUGCAUGUGAUGAUUAAGUGAAGACUGGGGCAGAAUGAUUUAAAAAAAGGAAAAAGAUGGAAGAUGAGUAGACACUUGCAAGGAACACUGUCAAACUAUAAAUCCAUUCAGUGGGUUGUAUAACAUUUAUAUUUAGUCUAAUUUAGACUUUGAUAAUUUAAUGCUACUUUUAUAUUUUAACAAAAAUAUAAAUUAAAAUUUUCAUUAGUCUGUUUUGUUGUUGGGUUUUUUUGUGAGGUACUCCCUGUUGGGGGAAAGGAACAAGGAACAACCAUCAGAAUCCCCCAGUCCCUACAGAAUAGCCUCACAGUAACUUGAGAAAACUGAACUUGGGGUUAAAUAACUUGUCACACUUGCAGUCUCCUGCCUCACUCCUUCAGGUGCCCUGCCUAGAAAAAGACUUGUGUCUAGCAUCCAAGUGAACACAUACUAUUGCCCUCUGUGAACCAGGAGGAAUGGAACAGGCAAUGGAAGGGUGAUAGUACCUACAAUACCCUUUGUAGACCCCAUCUCACUACCAUCAAAAUCUUGUCCACUAGCCCCCAAAAAACUGGCAAGGAAAGAAGGUGGAGGGGAAAUUUAUGGAAGUAGAUGGCUUAAUAGUUAUUUCUUUUAUCUUGGGCUGCCUUUCUCUAAGUUGGUUGUCCUGUCCCAGUGUGAAGACCCAUCUUUUUGUGAGAAAAGACAAAAGAAAGCACAUGUAACUACCUUCUUUGCAAUGGAAAAGGAGAAAGAAAAAAUCUUCUCCUAAGUUGCUGUUUUCUUUUAUUAGUUAAUAAAACAAAUCAGGGACUAUGCAGGUCUAUGGGGAAACCUUUAGUCUGCUUUAAGAAAACUCAGUAUCUGAAAAUCUUAACUUAGCAUGUGAUACUGUCUUAUCAGCAUCUGCAGAAGUGCCAAAGCCACUGCUAGACACUUAAUGUGUAUUAUUUCAUUUAAUUAUAUUUUAAAUGUGCUUCCUUGGUAAUUCUUAAGCUCGAGAAAGAGUUUGAGAACUGCUGCUAGGAAAUAGAGAUUCACAUUUAACCCUGUGGUACUUUUAAGAAGCAGGUACGUUGUUGCAUAUAUACUUGGGUAGAGAUUGGUAACUAUCUGAUAGGGAAGCUCAAGUUGGCCACCCAAGUCUGAGAAACCCUUAAUUACUGAGAAUCAAAAGAGCAGAAUGUCUGUAGACAUUUUGGAUUUGUAAAAAUCACAUUGUUGAGUUAUACCUGUGAUGGGCUGAAAGUUUUUGGCAUUCUUUCCUGUUCUUCAUAUGCCAGUACCAUAAACAAAAAGUAUCUCAGAUCUGUCACUUUCUUCUCCUAAACCAAUGUGAUGGCAGCUUUUUGCCUUCAGCCUUUUCCCUAUCCAGUAUCUCCUACAUAGUUACCUUUUGAUCUUAAGGAACUGUUUUGAUUGGGUCACUUCCUUGCCUAAAAUUCCAUUGAUUGUUCAUUGUUAAUUCUAAAAUAGAGUUCAAAUUUAAAGGCAUGUAAGUUCCCCUGUAACGGAUUUCCUCUACUCCCCCUUCCGCUGUAAUCUCCCAUUUUUUUACUGAAAUGCUUCAGUGAGCAUGGGUCUUUAGAGGUCUUGAUAUACAAUUUUCCUGAAGCAGGAAUACCUUGCUUUCCUCUACUAGUUUACCACAAUUACAGCUCUCUUUUAAGCCUCAGAAAAAAAUCUCACUUCCGUCUUGAAGUCUUAAUCCACGCUUUUUAUAUCCAUGUGCCUACUCCUUCUCUGAAAUCUCCUAUGGUUUAUCUUUUUAUUCAUUUAAUAUCCCACGAAUUGAUUUUAUUAUAUAUUUUUUAUGGUUGCAUGUGGUCUUUCUAGUUAUAGCAAUAUACACAUACAUGCAUAAAUACAUAUACACCUAUGUAAAUGUGUGUUGGGAGUAUGUAUUCACACACAUACAUAUACCCCAAGGCCAUGUGUCAUCUUUAUCAAUAUUUAAGUUUUGGAAUUGUUUUGUUUGCCUCCUAUAUCAUGGAAUAAAUGGUAAAGAGGGCUAAUUUAUUACUCUAAGUGGAUUUCUUAUUACAUUAAUAUCAGACAUAUAGAAUGUACUUUGUUUUACUAUUUGUAAGAUACAAAGGUAUAUAAACUGACAUACAUCAGCUUGAAACCUGAGAUAAUGCUAAAAUGUUCUAAUUAUUUUAAAUGUUUAAAGAGGACAACCAUGUAAUGUUGCUAAACAUGAAAAAUGUCAUCAAGUGGAAUAAAGAAUAGCUGAAGUUAACAUUUGGGGGAAAUUGAGCUGAAAACAAAAAUAUGAGUAUUUUGAUACCUUUUCUUUACCAUGAGACUCUUGACUAUGAAGUCAAAUUUAUCUAAAGGAAAAACAGGAAUUCUGGAGACCUGUGUAAAAGCAGACUAUUAUCUUCCUACUGUGAGAGUACUAAAAUUAAAAUACGUUUAAUGACGUUUUCCUCAAUGUAAAAGCAUUGAAGUAAAUGUUUCUUUUAUGUUGCAGAUACAUAGUUGCUCUAGAGAUCACCUUUUUCUUUAUGCAUUGUGAAUAGCAGUCUGCAUCCUAAGUUUAAAAUAUUUGAGAAUCCUCUAUGGGACUCUCUGUAAAUGUUUUAAAUACUGUUGUUUUCAAUAAAUAUUUUAUACUAUC